GUUCCGGCGCACGUAAUCGCCGAGGGCACGUGCAUGCCCCCUGGUUAAGAGUUGCAGGUAGCGGUAGCGAUGGACACUCUGGAUCGAGUAGUAAAGCCCAAAACGAAAAGAGCCAAGAGAUUCCUUGAGAAGAGAGAACCGAAACUCAAUGAAAAUAUUAAAAAUGCCAUGCUGAUUAAAGGGGGAAAUGCAAAUGCAACAGUGACAAAAGUACUUAAAGAUGUGUAUGCACUGAAAAAACCAUACGGUGUACUAUAUAAAAAGAAAAAUAUUACAAGACCUUUUGAGGAUCAGACAUCACUGGAAUUCUUUUCAAAGAAGUCAGAUUGUUCUUUAUUCAUGUUUGGCUCCCAUAAUAAGAAGCGGCCAAAUAAUCUAGUAAUAGGUCGUAUGUAUGACUACCAUGUGCUGGAUAUGAUUGAAUUAGGUAUUGAGAAUUUUGUCUCUCUAAAAGACAUUAAGAACAGUAAAUGUCCUGAGGGAACAAAACCCAUGCUGAUAUUUGCUGGCGAUGAUUUCGAUGUAACAGAAGAUUAUAGAAGACUAAAAAGUCUUCUUAUUGAUUUCUUCAGAGGCCCCACAGUAUCAAAUAUCCGCCUGGCUGGAUUAGAGUAUGUUCUGCACUUCACUGCACUGAAUGGGAAGAUUUACUUUCGAAGCUAUAAGUUGCUGUUGAAGAAAUCUGGUUGCAGAACACCACGGAUUGAAUUGGAAGAGAUGGGACCCUCAUUGGAUCUGGUUCUGAGGAGGACACACCUGGCAUCGGAUGACCUUUAUAAAUUAUCUAUGAAAAUGCCAAAAGCUCUCAAGCCAAAGAAGAAGAAAAAUAUUUCCCAUGAUACUUUUGGUACAACUUAUGGAAGGAUUCAUAUGCAGAAGCAAGACCUAAGCAAACUACAAACCAGGAAAAUGAAGGGGUUGAAGAAGCGACCUGCAGAAAGGAUAACAGAAGACCACGAGAAAAAGUCAAAAAGAAUUAAAAAAAAUUGAUGGAACUUAGCCAGCCACUACUGUUUCAUUGUGUUCUACUUAAGAGAAUUAUCAAGCGUCAAUCCAUUCAGAGUUUCUUAUAAGAUCUUAUUAUAUAUUUUUAUAACAUGAUAAUUUUACGAUAUAUUAUUAUGAACAGUAAUAUACUAGUAUUAAGUGUAAAGUAAGCCUUUUAUUUGAGACAUUACACCCUGGUGUGCCAUUUUCUCUUGUGAUAUCCCCUGCCCUCCACAAAUUCUUCUUUCUCAUUGGGUGGAUGGAUGGGUGAGGAGGGAUCUCCAUAACCAUUGGGAUUUUUUUGAAUUUCUGGCCUUAGCUAAAGAAAGCCACAGAAAGCCGGACCCGCAGGAGCUGUGUAAACAAUCUCAGUAUGAAUUACCUGGAAAGUUAACCUCCUCUCCCAACAUGGAUCUACAUUCUGAUUUUUAUUUUCUACUUUUAUUUUGCCUGAAAUCCUACUCGUUGACAUUUGAGAUUUUAAGCUUUGUGGCUGAAAAUAUAUAGAUCUCUGAGAGGGAUGUCUGCUAUCUGAUUAUUGAUAAAUUACACUACUGUUGAUUGUUUUAAGAGACUCUACUACUAAGUAGAGCCCACCCCGCUUCUCUGAGACGAAACCUGUGUUUUUUGGUUGGUUUGUUUUUAAGAGAUGGGGUCUUGUUCUGUCACCUAGGGUGGAGUGCAGUGGCACAAUCACAGCUCACUGCAGCCCUGAACUCCUGGGCUCAAGUAAUCCUCCUGCCUGAGCCUCUUACGUAGCUGGGAUUACAGGCAUGAGCCACUGAGCCCUACUUUUUUUUUUUAAAGCAAUGAGGUCUUGCUGUGUUGCCCAGGCUGGACUCAAAUUCCUGGGCUCAAGUGAUCCUCCCACUUCACCUUCCUGAGCAGCCGGAACUACAGAUGUUGGUCCACUGCACCUGGCAGAAAAGAAGUUUUGAUAGGGGCAGAAAUGAAAAAGGAGAAAACAGGUGAGUUUUAAGGUGCAGGGCACUUUAGGGUACUGGGUAGCCCUAGGUAGCUAAAGGUUGCAUGAAGGCCCUGGGCGUUUGCAGAUGGUGUAGAAGCCAGCCAAAGCCUAACUACUUGUUUUGAAAGUUUCUUGAAGACAGGCCUUGUGCCUAGGAAAACAGAAGCUUUCUUCUUCCUUCUACUAGUAUUGCAUACUUGUUUUUCUGGAAUAGGGUGUUAAGUUCCUUGAUUCAGUCCUUGACAAGGAAUCUCCUUUAUACAAGUGCCAGUAAUGUUGUAAAGGUACAGACAUACGCAAAUCAUAAUUUGUUACAUGAAGUACCAGUGCUUUCUUUUUUGUUGUUUUUUGAGACAGAGUCUCGCUCUGUCGCUCAGGCUGGAGUGCAGUGGCGCGAUUUCAGUUCACUGCAACCUCCACCUCCCAGGUUCAAGCAUUCUUCUGCCUCAGCCUCCCGAGUAGCUGGGAUUACAGGCACCCACCACCACGCCUGGCUGAUUUUUUGUAGAGACAGGGUUUCACUUCAAUUCCAUGUUAGAGAGCUCCGUGCCUGUGUAUACAUGCCUUUAUGUAAGCUUGCUCAGCUACAGAUCAACAAUGCUGGCACUAAGCAAAAGUUCGAGCCUCAGCUUUACCUUCUACCCUUUCCCUUCUCUUUUGAAUCCAUUCCUUAGCUUUCCCUAGUCCUCUCCGGAUAGCUGUUACUCUCCUCUUGCCAGAAAAAUGAAGGAGCUGGUAUCAUUUAUACUUUUUGUUUGAUUAUACGUUUAACCAAAGACCAUACAGUCUCGUACCUGAAUCAGACAUUUGCACUUUAUAUCUAAAUGAGAAGAAGGGGCUCAGAUAAGUCGUUUGCUGCCAUCUGGAGGUAGAUGGACAAUAGCUGAGAAGGGGAGCCAUGAAAAGAACAUCAGGAGUGAUGGACGCAUAGUCCUUCCCCAAAGCCUCGCUCAUCACUGGUAGGAGGCAAAGCAGUGGGUCCUCCUCACCAGCCGCUUACGGGACCCUGCCAUGCCUGGACCCCUCUAUCAGGAAGACCUACCCCAGCACUACUGGAAAAUCAGCCAAUCUUAACCCAAAGAUGGCCAUGAUUUCUGUAUGUGAGACGUCUUAAGGGUGUUUUUGUUUGUUUUAAUCAGCCCUCUUGUUUGAGAUUUGGCAAUACAUUUCUGUUUUCUAGGUAAUUUCUGUGUCUGAUGGUAGAGGAUCUAAUAAGUAUUGGAAUGCUUCCUAUUUGCUGAUAGAAGUACCAAAUAGUAUUAUUGAAGUCUAACAAAGACUUUUUGUUGAGAACACCUUGUAGUGUUGUACUAUCUGGAACUCUUGAGCUGCCAUUUAUAUCACUUUUUGUGGAGAGCACAUCUUGAUUUUCAGUUGUCCUUACUUUAGAAUACAACACACAUAAAUUGGAGACUAUGUAUUCAUUUCAAUGGAGGUGGUAAAUUGCCUGUUUUAAGUUUUACUUAAUGUUGGGUUUUGGUAGAUGAGGAAAGCAUUUUGGUUAUUUGUUUUGUUUUAAAUACCAAAUUUCUUAUAUUUUUUCUGGAAUAUUAAUACUAUUACCAAGCUAUUAUUUCAUGGAAUUUGGGUUUCUUUUUUUUUGUUUUUUUAAAAUUAAGUGCUGUUUGUUUUCUUGGUUAUUGAACAUAAUCCAAAGUAGAGAUGUUAUUACUCAAUUCAAGAAAAGAAAGGGCUAAUAAAACUUAACUUCAAGUCA